UUUUUUUUUUUUUUUUUGAGACAGAGUCUCGCUCUGUUGCCCAGGCUGGAGUGCAGUGGCGCGAUCUCUGCUCACUGCAAGCUCUGCCUCCCGGGUUCACGCCAUUCUCCUGCCUCAGCCUCCCGAGUAGCUGGGACUACAGGCGCCCACCACCAUGCCCAGCUAAUUUUUUUUUUUUGUAUUUUUAGUAGAGAUGGGGUUUCACCAUGUUAGCUAGGAUGGUCUCAAUCUCCUGACCUCGUGAUCCGCCCGCCUCAGCCUCCCAAAGUGCUGGGAUUACAGGCGUGAGCCACCGCGCCUGGCCUCGCAGGUCUUUAUGACAGGGACAGAUCUCUUUGAAAUUCAAAAAGUAAUUGAGCAGAUUCUAAGCUGUGUUUCAACCUUUUUUUGUUUUGUUUUGUUUUCCAAGACAGGGUCUUGCUCUGUCUUCCAGGCUGGAAUGCAGUGGCGUGAUCAUGGCUCACCGCAACCUCUGCAUCCUGGGCUCAAGCAGUACUCCCACCUCAGUGUUCCUGCCCACACCCCCCAGUAGCUGGGACUACAGACAUGCCAUCAUGCCCAGCUAUUUCACCUUGUUGCCCAGACUGGUCCUGAACUCCUAGGGCUCAAGCAGUCUUCCUGCCUCAGUCUCCCAAAGUGUUGGGAUUACAGGCGUGAGCCCCUGUGCCUGGCCUACUUUCUGUUUUUAUGAGUCUUGCUACUUUAGGUACCUUAUAUAAGUUAGAAUCAUUCAGUAUUUAUCUUUUAGUGAUAAGUGUAUUUUCACUUAGUAUAAUGUCCUUGAGGUUCAUCCAUGUUGUAAUGUGUGUCAGAAUUUCCUUCCUUUUGAAGGCUUAGUAACAUUCCACUGCAUAUAUAUACAUUUUGUUUAUCCAUUUAUCCAUAGAUGGGCAUUUAGGUUGCUUCUAUCUCUUGGUUAUUGUGAAUAAUGCUGCAGUUGGCUGCAGUUGAACACGGGUGUGCAAAUAUCUUAUCUGUUUGAGAUCUUUUUUUUUUUUUUUUUUUGAGUUUAGCUCUGUUGCCCAGGCUGGAAUGCAGUGGCAUGAUCUUGGUUCACUGCAACCUUGGCCUCCCGAGUUCAAGUGAUUCUCAUGCCUCAGCCUCCCAAGUAGCUGGGAUUACAGUCAUGCGCCACCAUGUCCGGCUAAUUUUUGUAUUUUUAGUAGAGAUGGGGUUUUGCCAUGUUGGCCAGGCUGGUCUCGAACUCCUGGCCUCAAGUGAUCACCCGCCUCCUAAAGUGCUGGGAUUACAGGUGUGAGCCACUGUGCCCGGCCCUGUUUGAGAUUUUAUAUUCAGUUCUUUUAGAUAUAUAGCCAGAACUGGGAUUUUUGGAAUAUAUGGUAGUUCUAUUUUUAAUUUUUUGAGGAGCCUCCAUCCCCUUUUCCAUAGUAGCUACACCAUUUACAUUCCCACCAGUGAUGCAAAGGGUUCUAGUUUCUCCACAUUCUUGAUAACACAUAUUAUUUUCUGAGGUUUUUUUGCUUCGUUUUUUUGGAUAGUGGUCAUUCUAUUGGGUGUGAGGUAAUAUUUUGUUGUGGCUUUGAUAUGCCUUUCCCUAUGGUUGGUGAUGUUGAGCAUCUUUUCAUAUGCCUGUUAACCAUUUGUAUAUCUUCUUUGGAUAAAUAUUUAUUCCAGAAAUGUCAUCCAAGAAAUCACUGUCAAUUGCAAUGAUUAUGAAGCUUUUCCCCUAGGCUUUCUUCUAAGAGUUUUAUAGUUUCAGGUCUUACGUUUAGGUCUUUAGUCCUUUUUGAGUUAACUUUCAUAUGUGAUAUAAGGGACUAACUUUGUUCUUUUUCAGGUGAAUAUUCAGUUUUCCUAGCACCAUUGUGUAGUCUUGGCACCCUUGACAAAGAUCAUUUGAAUCCUUUACAGGAGGGUUUCUUUCUGGGUCUAUUCCAUUAUAUUGGUCUGUGUGUCCAUCUUUAUGCUAGUACCCAUACUGUUUUGAUUACUAUGGCUUUGUAAUAAGUGUUGAAAUUAGAAGUAUGAGACCUCCAAUAUUAUUCUUUUUUAAGAUUGUUUUGGCUAUUUGGGGUCUCUUGAGAUUCCACGUGAAGGAAACAAUUCCAUUUUUUGCAGAAAACGUCAUUGAGAUUUUGGUGAAGGUUACAUUGAAUCUGUAGAUUAUGUUGGGUAGUACUGAAAUCUUAACAAUAUUAAGUCUUCUAGUCUGUGAACAUGAGAUGUCUUUCAUUUAUUGGUGUCAUCUUUAAUUUCUUUCAGCAAUGUUUUGUAAUUUUCAGUAUACAAGUCUUUUGUCUCCUUGGUUAAGCUUAUUCCUGAGUAUUUUAUUCGUUUUUAUUCUAUUGUAAAUGGAAUUGUUUCUUUUCAGAUUUUUCAUUGUUAGUAUGUAGAAGCAACUAAUUUUAAUCUGUUAAUUUUGUGACCUGCAACUUUGCCAAAUUCAUUUAUUAAGUCUUAACAGUCUUCUUAUGGAAUCUUUUGGGUUUUCUACAAGUAAGAUCAUGUUGAAUGAUCUUACAUUAUAUGUGACCAGAGAUUAUUUUACAUCUUCCUUUCAAUUUAGAUGUCCUUUGUUUUUCUUGCCUAAUUGCUCUGGCUAGAACUUCGAACACUAUGUUGAAUAGAAGUGGCAACAGUAGAUAUCCUAGUCUUGUUCCUGAUCUUACAGUUUUGAAAAGCUUUUUGUCUUCACUGUUGUGUGAUGUUAGCUGUUGGUUUUUGCAUAUAUGGCAUUUAUUACUUUGAAGUUGUUUCCUUCCUGGUUUGUUGAGUGUCUUUAUCAUGAAAGGGUGUCAAAGUCUGUUAGAUGCUUUUUUUGCAUAAAUUGAGAUGACCAUGUCUUUUCCUUCUUCAUUCUGUUAAUGUGGAUUACAUUUAUUUUCAUAUGUUGAGCCACCCUUGUAUUCCAGGUAUAAAUCCCACUUGAUGAUGAUGUAUAAUCCCUUCAAUAUGCUGUUGAAAAGCCAGGCGUGAUGGCUCAUGCCUGUAAUCUGACUUAUUUGGGAGGCUGAGGCAGGAGGAUUGCUUAAGGCCAGGAGCUCGAAACCCAUCUGGGCAACAUAGCAACACCCCAUUUCUAAAUUUAAAAUUUUGAAAAUAAAAAUUUAAAAAUUGAGAAAAAAUAUGCUAUUGAAUUCCAUUUGUUGGUAUUUUAUCGAGGGUUUUUGCAUUACUAUUCAUAAGGGAUAUUAUUAGUCUGUAAUUUUCUUUUCUUGUUUCUUCAUCUAGCUUUGGUAUCAGAAUAAUGCUUGUCUCAUAGAAUGAGUAGAAAGUGUUCUUUCCUCUUCAGUUUUUGGAAAGAGUUUGAAAAGGAUUAAUGUUAUUUCUUUACAUGUUUUGUAGAAUUCACCAGUAAAGCCAUUUGGUCCUGGGCUUUUCUUCAUUGGGAAGUUUUUCAUUACUGAUUUAAUCUCUUGGCAAGUUAUAGGUCUGUUCAGAUUUUCUGUUUCUUCAUGAUUUAGUCUUGUUAGGUUAUUUUUCUAGGAAUUUGUUUAUUUCAUGUAAGUUAUUCAAUAUGUUCACUUGCAUUUGUUCAUAAUACUUUUUAUAACCCUUUUUAUUUCUGUAAAAUUGGUAGUAAUAUCCUGACUUUUAUUUCUGAUUAGUUAUUUAAAUCCUCUUAUUUCUUUCUUUCUUUCUUUCUUUUUUGACAUAGAACCUCACUCUGUCACCGAGACUGGAGUGCUUGUGGCAUGAUCUCGGCUCACUGCAACCUCUGCCUCCCGGGUUCAAGCAAUUCUCAUGCCUCAGCCUCCCAAGUAGCUGGGACUACAGGCAGCUGCCAUCAGGCCUGGCUAGUUUAUUUAUUUAUUUUUUUGUAUUUUUAGUAGAGACAGGGUUUCAACGUGUUGGCCAGGCUGGUCUUGAACUCCUGACUUCAAGUGAUCUGCCCGCCUUGGCGUCCCAAAGUGCUGGGAUUAACAGGCAUGAGCCACUGCACCCGGCUCUCUCUUAUUUCUUAAUCUAGCUUAAGCUUUGUCAAUUUUGUUGUUGUUGUUGUUAAUUUUGAAAUACUUUACUUUUAAAAUAGGUCACAACACUAAGCUUUUGGCCCAUUCCGCCAUUGUACAAGCUACAGAUGCUUGCUUAGCAGCCAAGGGGCACUCUUGAGUAGCAUAUCAGAAAAGUGAAUAAAAAUCCAUAUAAAACAAAUAUUUAAAUAGUUUCCAUAGGAACAUAUAUAAUGUGUGACCUAUAUCCUAGUCUUCCAUAUUGCCACAUCCGUAUGAACCCAACUCUUAAGAAAAGUGAAUAAAAAUCCAUAUAAAACAAAUAUUUAAAUAGUUUCCAUAGUAACACAAAUAAUGUGUGACCCAUAUCCUAGUCUUCCAUAUUGCCAUGUCCAUGCGAACCCAACUCUUACGAAAUCCCUUAAUUCAAGCUGGACUCAUGGUUAACAAUUACAAGAGUGAUAUCUACAUAUUAAUACUAGCAGAAGCACAAGUUGCUGAUUGAUGUUUCAUUCUAUUUUCCCAAGCAGAAGACACAGGAUGCUAAUGUCCUGUUCCUCUACUUGGGGUGGGAGAUCGUGCUUCUAGAUACACUGCAUGAGUUUCGAUGCUGGUCCUGACAUCACAUGUAGAUUGUUGGCCUCUGGAAUCCAUUAAAAGUACAAGUAGCAGCAACAGUGUCAGCGCCCAUGUUUUUAAAGAGCAUCCAAUUACCUACAUAUAUUUUGGGCAGAUCACAGUGCUCAACAAUCUGAUCAAGGCCAUCACAUGUUCUUCCCAUAUACUGGAUGAAUAAUACUUCUCACUGAUCUAGGUCUCUUUUGCAGCAGGGGCUUUACAUGUGCAUGAUCAUAAAGGAUUGAUUAAAUGAUCCAUAUACUUCAUCAUUCAUGUAAUACAUAAAGGUCUGUUCGCUUGACUCAUCUUCCUCUUCAGAGCCUGUCUGUUCUUUUUUUUCUUUCUUUCUUUUUGAGACAGAGUCUCGCUCUGUCACCCAGGCUGGAGUGCAGUGGUGUGAUCUGGGCUCACUGCAAGCUCCGCCUCUCGGGUUCACGCCAUUCUCCUGCCUCAGCCUCCCGAGUAGCUGGGACUACAGGCGCCCGCUGCCGUGCCUGGCUAAUUUUUUGGGUUUUUUUUUUAGUAGAGAUGGGGUUUCACCGUGUUAGCCAGGAUGGUCUUGAUCUCCUGACCUCAUGAACUAUCUCCCUCAGCCUCCCAAAGUGCUGGGAUUACAGGCAUGAGCCACCGCGACGGCCCUGUCUGUUCUUUUAAUAUGAUUUUUUUGGCAAUGAAAGCUGAUGCCACAUGAAAUAUCUGCCUGGCUCAGCUGUGACUCUCACUCUAGAGUCUGGUGGAAAAUACUUGUCUGAUGCUGGGUUGAUUACACUGGUAAUACUUCAGAUUUAAGCCUCACGUCCUCAGAUCCAGGAAAGCAACUGCCAGUAUUAAGCAGUUACAUUCUGAAACCAAACUCAACUCCCGUGUCAAAGACACAGUGGACAUUGGAGGCUGCCUGCAUGAAGGUCUCAGGAUUGGUACAGCUACUUCCUACAUGGAAGCUGACACCAGUGACAUCAAUAUUUAGUUCUUUUGCUCAUUCCAAAAGAAGCCUGCUGGCUUUGAGCAUGGCACCAGAUUUAACACUGAUGUGACGGGCUGCUUUGAGUGUGUUCUGGCAACUGACAUCAACUUGACCUCAUUACCGAAAAUCAUCAUCUGGACUCCAUUAUUGGCAGUGUACUUAAUUUGAGACAUUUGUUUACAAGAAUUUGCAUACAUAAACCUCUCUGGGGGCAUCCCCAGAAUCUGCACCAAUUGUAUUUCAGCCUUGCUAGCACAGUCAAAUCCUGUCCCGAUGGCAGCAAGAGUCUUCAUGAUGGCUCUGCUGUCAUUAUAAUUGACUGCAUAAAAGGGGGUGACAUGAGGAAGAGCUUUUAACUAUCUUAGAUGUGUCUUUAGAAUGUCUCUAAGGUCCAUGACAUAGAAGGCAUCCUAAUCAUCAUCAGAAGAAAAUUCAUUAAUUUUUUGGUCCAGAAUGUCCUUGGCAGUAAAACCUUCAUCAAGGAAGCAAGUGGCAGUGAAACUCUUCAUUAUUAAACUCUUCAUGGUUUCUUGAUGUUCCUCUGAAACACAACAAAAUGGAAAACUAAGAGAUGGAAUUGAAAGAAAUAUUUCCAGCUUCUCACAAAGACAGUUCUCCAGGAAUUCCAAAUCCUGCCUCUUGUGCCCUCAGAGCAGCAGUGGAAACAUUCUCAGAGCACCUGGGUACCACAGAGAGUGAAGAUGCUGCUGUCUGAGCCAGAGCUACAGGACCUCUCUGCUGUGCCUGUCAGUGCCUUACUUCUGCCCGCCAGAGAUGCUGGCCCAAGGUUCAUGCAUGGGAGAUCUCAGACCAGUUGUUACAGAUCCGGCAGGAUGUGGAGUCAUGCUAUUUUGCUGCACAGACCAUGAAAAUGAAGAUUCAGACCUCAUUUUAUGAGCUCCCCACAGACUCUCAUGCCUCUUUACGGGACUCAUUGCUAACCCAUAUCCAGAACUUGAAAGACUUGUCACCUGUUAUUGUAACGCAGCUGGCUUUAGCAAUAGCAGAUCUUGCCCUACAGAUGCCUUCCUGGAAGGGAUGUGUGCAAACACUGGUGGAAAAAUACAGCAAUGAUGUGACUUCUUUGCCUUUUUUGCUGGAGAUCCUUACAGUGUUACCUGAAGAAGUACAUAGUCGUUCCUUACGAAUUGGAGCUAAUCGGCGCACAGAAAUUAUAGAAGAUUUGGCCUUCUACUCUAGUACAGUAGUAUCUCUAUUGAUGACCUGUGUAGAAAAAGCAGGAACAGAUGAGAAAAUGCUUAUGAAGGUUUUUCGCUGUUUGGGAAGUUGGUUUAACUUGGGAGUUUUGGACAGUAACUUCAUGGCUAACAAUAAAUUACUAGCACUCCUUUUUGAGGUUUUGCAACAGGAUAAGACCUCGUCUAACCUACAUGAAGCUGCUUCGGACUGUGUAUGCUCAGCUCUCUAUGCCAUUGAGAAUGUGGAGACUAACUUGCCAUUAGCCAUGCAACUUUUUCAGGGAGUGCUGACAUUGGAGACUGCCUAUCAUAUGGCCGUGGCACGUGAAGAUUUAGACAAAGUUCUGAAUUACUGCCGUAUUUUCACUGAACUAUGUGAAACUUUUCUUGAAAAAAUUGUUUGUACUCCAGGCCAAGGUCUUGGGGACCUUCGAACUCUGGAGCUGCUGCUUAUCUGUGCAGGCCAUCCUCAAUAUGAGGUAGUAGAAAUUUCAUUUAACUUUUGGUACCGACUGGGGGAACAUUUGUACAAAACUAACGAUGAAGUUAUUCAUGGCAUCUUCAAAGCUUACAUUCAGAGGCUGCUUCACGCCUUGGCUCGACACUGCCAGCUGGAACCAGACCAUGAGGGGGUUCCUGAGGAGACUGAUGACUUUGGGGAGUUUCGCAUGAGGGUAUCAGACCUGGUAAAGGACUUGAUUUUCUUGAUAGGGUCUAUGGAGUGUUUUGCUCAGUUAUAUUCUACUCUGAAAGAAGGCAACCCACCCUGGGAGGUGACAGAAGCGGUUCUCUUUAUCAUGGCUGCUAUAGCAAAGAGUGUUGAUCCGGAAAACAAUCCAACACUUGUGGAAGUCCUAGAAGGAGUUGUCCGCCUCCCGGAGACCGUACAUACGGCUGUGCGAUACACCAGCAUUGAAUUGGUUGGAGAGAUGAGUGAAGUCGUUGAUCGAAAUCCUCAGUUCCUUGACCCUGUGUUGGGCUAUUUGAUGAAAGGCCUGUGUGAAAAGCCCCUGGCUUCUGCUGCAGCCAAAGCCAUUCAUAACAUUUGCUCUGUCUGCCGAGAUCACAUGGCUCAGCACUUUAAUGGACUCCUGGAGAUUGCCCGCUCCCUCGAUUCCUUCCUGUUGUCUCCAGAAGCUGCUGUGGGCUUGCUAAAAGGGACAGCACUUGUCCUAGCCCGAUUACCUUUGGAUAAGAUUACCGAAUGUCUUAGUGAACUAUGUUCUGUUCAGGUUAUGGCAUUGAAAAAGCUGUUGUCUCAAGAGCCCAGCAAUGGCAUAUCCUCAGAUCCCACAGUGUUCUUAGAUCGCCUUGCAGUGAUAUUUAGGCAUACCAAUCCCAUUGUGGAAAAUGGACAGACUCAUCCGUGUCAGAAAGUCAUACAGGAAAUAUGGCCAGUUUUAUCCGAGACUCUAAAUAAGCACCGAGCUGAUAAUCGGAUUGUAGAGCGUUGUUGCAGGUGCCUGCGCUUUGCUGUUCGCUGUGUAGGCAAAGGAUCUGCAGCACUGCUGCAGCCACUAGUCACACAGAUGGUGAAUGUGUACCACGUACAUCAGCAUUCCUGCUUCCUGUACCUUGGCAGUAUCCUUGUGGAUGAAUAUGGCAUGGAAGAAGGCUGUCGGCAGGGACUGCUAGACAUGCUCCAGGCACUGUGCAUCCCCACCUUUCAGCUCCUAGAACAGCAGAAUGGUCUCCAGAAUCACCCUGACACUGUAGAUGACCUGUUCCGGCUAGCCACCAGGUUUAUUCAGCGUAGCCCUGUCACCUUGCUGCGGAGCCAAGUGGUCAUCCCUAUCUUACAGUGGGCCAUUGCCUCUACUACCCUGGACCACCGGGAUGCCAAUUGUAGUGUCAUGAGGUUUCUACGAGACCUCAUUCAUACAGGGGUAGCCAAUGAUCAUGAAGAAGACUUUGAAUUACGGAAAGAACUGAUUGGACAGGUGAUGAACCAGCUUGGACAGCAGCUUGUCAGCCAGCUGCUGCACACCUGCUGCUUUUGCCUCCCCCCCUAUACCCUACCAGAUGUGGCUGAAGUGCUCUGGGAGAUCAUGCAGGUUGACAGACCGACUUUUUGUCGAUGGUUAGAAAAUUCCUUAAAAGGUUUGCCAAAGGAAACAACCGUGGGAGCCGUCACAGUGACACACAAACAACUUACAGACUUCCACAAGCAAGUCACUAGUGCUGAGGAAUGUAAACAAGUUUGCUGGGCCUUGCGAGACUUCACCAGGUUGUUUCGAUAGCUCACACUCCUGCACUGUGCCUGUCACCCAGGAAUGUCUUUUUUAAUUAGAAGACAGGAAGAAAACAAAAACCAGACUGUGUCCCACAAUCAGAAACCUCCGUUGUGGCAGAGGGGCCUUCACCGCCACCAGGGUGUCCCGCCAGACAGGGAGAGACUCCAGCCUUCUGAGGCCAUCCUGAGGAGUUCCUGUUUGGGGGUGUGAGGGAAAAUCAGCGCGGAUUUUAAAAAGAUGGCUGUGGCCUGCCCGGCGUGGUGGGAGGGGAGCUGGUUUCCUGGUGAACUUUCUAAAAGGAAAAAUAAUUUUAAGUAAAGAAAAAAGAAAAAAAAGGAAGACUAAACAGAAACCAGAACUGAAACAUUCACCUGGUAGCAAAUGACACAUGCACGCACACACACAUACACGCACAAGCGCCAGUGCGCACGUGUACACAGAAAAACAAAAGGACAAGCUUUCUGUGAAACAAAAUAUUUACUUAGGGAUAAUGUGGGGAUUCACAUGAAUUAAAUAGCUGCAAUUGGAAGAAGAGGGUCAGGGUCAUUUGUUCAGGUUUUCUAUUGUUUUGUCCUCUCUUUCCUCUCCUACCCUUCCUUCUCUUUCUCUCUCCCCUCCUUUUAAAUGCAAAUGAGUAGAAAUUUCUUCUACCUUCCCCAGCUGUUUCUUCCCACCUUUAGAGUUGUUUAGACAAGGAGGAGUAAGCAAGGAACUUGUUCUGCUUUCUAUCGUGGUCACAUUGGUGAUGCUCGGGACCUGCCAGGGUCAGAAUUUAUGGAUAUCUGAACCCUGACCCCGUUCAUUCUCUCAGUCCACUUCCAAUCCACAUCAGUUUGUUGUCUGCCUUGGAGAGAAGAGCCAAAACUGGGGUGGGCGGGUGGGUGGGGAGUGCAGGAUAUAAAUGUGUAAGUUUUUGUUUUUUAAGGUUUUUUUCUUAGUGAAUUAUUCACCCACAGACAUGAGAGAAAAAAAGAGGGAGGGUGUGUGGAGAAAAAAUGUUUACAGGGCUAACAAGGGAUGAUGUGUCAUUUAGUAUGUUACUAAAAAGUGUGGAAAUGACUUGAUUUUAAGGGGAGGGUGAGGCCGAAGAGGGAAGCCCAAAGCAGAUCUUAAUGUUUCAAAGGAGUGCAGCCCUUCACAGCCAUCAGAUAUGAGGGCACUGUUCUGUCUGGUGUUGUAGCCAUCUCAAGAACAAAUCAACAGCAACAAAAGAGAAAGAAUAAAUUUUUAAAAUUUAA